AGGUGGGCGGGAUGCGAAGAGCUAUGGGGAAGGAUUCGAAUUCCGGUGGAUUUAAAUCGCGGGAGGAGAAGCUACCGCGGCCUAGUAGAAGAAGACCUCUGUUGAACACAGACUGCAGUUCCAGCCACCACAGCUAAUCUGGAUCAUGAAUGGGAGCCACCGUGGUCUUGGCAAGUCCGAAAACAUAGCUGAGUAGCUCGUCUAGAAAAGAGAUUUGUGUUCAGCUGAGUUAAAAGAAGUAUUUACCUCAAACCUCUCCUCUUGCACAACCAACCCCCGUUAUAAAAGGAAGUGCAAAAUGGAAUAAACUGAUUUUAAGUGAAUACAAGCUGUCUUUAUAUACAAAAGUAACUCAAGGAUGGUGAUGUACCCAGUCAUGCUUUCAACUGAUUUGGGAAGCCUACACCAUUCACCUUAGGUUACAUAUGAGGAUAACUUAAAACAUUAAGCUAUGCAUAAAAACUCCAAGAGAAACAAUAAUUUAAGAGUUUCUCACACAGAAGCGAACUCUGUGGAUGCUGAGAAGGAAAAAAAUGAGAGUCAAAACAACUUUUUUGAACUGCUGCCUGCAGAAAUCACUUUUAAAAUUUUCAGUCAGCUGGACAUUCGGAGUCUGUGCAGGGCUUCAUUGACAUGCAGGAGCUGGAAUGACACAAUAAGAAACAGUGACUCUUUAUGGAAACCUCACUGCAUGACUGUAAGAGCUGUGUGCCGAAGAGAAAUAGAUGAUGAUCUAGAAAGUGGUUAUUCCUGGAGGGUGAUACUGCUGAGGAAUUACCAGAAGAGUAAAGUGAAACACGAAUGGCUAAGUGGCAGAUACAGCAACAUUUGUUCUCCCAUUAGCCUACCAGAAAAAAUCAUGUACCCAAUGGAUGCAGAUACAUGGGGGGAAAUUCUAGAAGCAGAACUGGAAAGAUAAGGGGAAAAAAAAUCACAAAUCUCAGGUCUUUGAAAGUUUAAAACUUAAAUGACUCUUAGGUUGCAAAAGCGAUAUCUUUAUUCGUUCAUUUUGUUGUUCACCUUUUUAAAAGAAAAUGAAAUGGAACUAUUAUAAAAGUAAAGCUUUAUUUUUGUUUUGCACUUUAGUAAAAUUUUUCUGGUUUUAUUGUAAUGUGGAAAAAUCAUGAAAUGUUAUUUUUAUAAGAAAUAAUAUACUGAUAGAGUGAUUUCCAAAUACAAUGUUUCAUGUAUUUGUGUUAAUAUAUUUGCAAUACUAAAUGUAAGAGUGAUUUGUAUGUUCAGCUUAAUGAUAAUUCAAAAUUUCAGGAAGCCACUUUAAACUGACUUAAAGAUUCAUUAAGUGGUGGUUAUAACUAGGCUCAUGGGAAGACUAGCUAAGUGAAAUUAAUAGCAAUACAUUUAAAUUAAUACAUUGACAUUUUAAUGACUUUAACAUUUCUAUUUCAGUGGAAUCAGAUUGAAAUGUCAAAUAGUGAAACUAUUUUUAAUGUGUUAAGCCUGUGGUUUAGUUUUAAGUUAAUGUCAUCUCAGGGCUAAAGUUUGUCCAAUUGAGAUUCCCAUUAAUUUUAUAUAAACCUGGAACGGCUCUCAGGAGCUGAAAGUAAGUGGAAAGUUUCCAGAACACUUUACCAUCAGAAUGCCACACUAGCCUGGUAAAACUCUCUUUCUGACAGCCUUAUAGCACCAUCUAGUGUGCUAUUCUUAGAUAGCAAGACAAAGGACUUUCAGCUCCUUUUUGUUUUCUCCAUAUUAAAAAGAAAACUGUUAUUCUAAAGAAUCCUUAACACUUGUCUUUGUUAAAGUUUAUAACUUUUUAGGAACCUUUAUUUUAACUUUUAAAAACUUUUGUUUCUCUUUUUUCAUAAAAACAGAUUAUAUGCUACUCACUAUAACAAAUUGUUUAUUCUGAAUCUGUGGUUACCACCAUAGUAAAAAAGUGUCUACAAACUGCUUUAGUUAGUGUGGGGUUUUCUUCUUAAAAACUGUUCUCUAUAGCAUUAAAUAUAAGAAUCCAGGAAACCAAUAUUUAACAAAUAGGCAAAUAUUAGAAAGAUGCCCCACUAUAUGCAAAUUCUGUAUGUUGAAUCAAGCAGUAGAUAAUUAAUUGUCUCCUACUAUCUUCUUAGAGUUGGAAGAGUCCUUGAAAAUCAGGCAGUCAAGUGUCCAGGACUAUUCAGUAAUUUUCUCAAUAGGAACACUGUCAGUCAGCCAGCCCAAGCUGAAAUCCUGUACUUCUACUAAUAGCAUCUCUGUUAUGUCACAGAACAGUCCAGUUGUAGUCUAGGCUUGCACUGAAGACCACCUCUCUGUAACGUUUGCCUUCUAGCCCCACUUCCACCCUCUAGAACCAGGCUGAUUCAGUCCUUCCUGUCUAUGAUUGCCAGAUAUUUGAAGACUGAUAGCCUGUCUCUUCCUAUGUCUUCUCUCCAAUUCCACUGAUGAUCAUAGAGUAUAAUUUCUAGACCCAACAACAUUCUCUUCUGCCCAUUUACUCUUAACAAAAGAAAGGGGCUGUGCGCCAUGGCUCACGCCUGUAAUCCCAGCACUUUGGGAGACCAAGGUGGGUGGAUCACCUCAGGUCAGAAGUUCAAGACCAGCCUGGUCAACAUGGUGAAACCCUGUCUCUACUAAAUAUACAAAAAUUAGCCGGGCGUGGUGGCAGGUGCCUGUAAUCCCAGCUACUUGGGAGGCUGAGGCAGGAGAAUCGCUUAAACCUGGCAGGCAGAGGUUGCAGUGAGCAGAGAUCACGCCACUGCGCUCCAGCCUGGGCAACAAGAGUGAAACUUCGUCUCAAAAAAAAAGGAAGAAAGAAAGGUAUCCUACUAAUUUUAUUUCAUAAAAGAUAAGAAAGCACUUGGAAAUUUUCAAAGUAUGGGAAAAAUUAAAGCUAUAAGCAUUUUGCUGAAUAGCAUCUGUGUACAAUAGUAAAUGUACACAUAUAUUUUUAGCUGUUUUUUUGUAAUGGAUGUUUAUUAUUUUUGUCCAGCCCCCUUACAAUCUAUCAUCAUCAUCUGUUAAUAGAAGUUAUCCUAAUUAGGGAGACUCACCCUUCUCACUUCCAACCAAGUGUGUGGUUUUUUUUGGCCGGGGUGGGGGGCAGUUUUUUGUUUUUGUUUUUUUGUUUUGUUUUUUGAGAUGAAGUCUCACUCUGUCACCCAGGCUGGAGUGCAGUGGCAUGAUCUUGGCCCACUGCAACCUCCACCUCCCAGGUUCAAGCAACUCUCUGUGUCAGCCUCCCGAGCAGCCAGGAUUAUAGGCGCCCGCCACCAUGCCCAGCUAAUUUUUGUAUUUUUAGUAGAAACGGGGUUUCACCAUCUUGGCCUCCUGACCUUGUGAUCUACCUGCCUCAGCCUCCUAAAGUGCUGGGAUUAUAGGCAUGAGCCACCGCACCCAGCUGGGUUUUUUGUUUUCUUGUUUUUUUUUUUUUACAUUAUCCUGUUUUUCCCAGCCUCCGUGUUUAGUCCAAGGAUGGAAACAUGACCCAAUCCCCCCUUUUCAUAAGUUGGAAGAAAGAAGCCCUUUCCUCUUUGCUGAUGAAACUGUUCCCUGCCACACAAAGAAAACGGAUCUUGGCCGGGCGCGGUGGCUCACGCCUGUAAUCCCAGCACUUUGGGAGGCCGAGGCGGGUGGAUCAUGAGGUCAGGAGAUCGAGACCAUCCUGGCUAACAAGGUGAAACCCCGUCUCUACUAAAAAUACAAAAAAUUAGCCGGGCGCGGUGGCGGGCGCCUGUAGUCCCAGCUACUCGGGAGGCUGAGGCAGGAGAAUGGCGUGAACCCGGGAGGCGGAGCUUGCAGUGAGCCGAGAUUGCGCCACUGCAGUCCGCAGUCCGGCCUGGGCGACAGAGCGAGACUCCGUCUCAAAAAAAAAAAAAAAAAAAAGAAAACGAAAACGGAUCUUAAGUAAGAGAAUGUGGAGCCACCAGGGGAAAGAACAAUUGCAGGGAAAGAGGCCUGAUUAUAUUCCAGACCCUGGUCCCAGCCAUUCCUUAUCUGCUUACCUAAAUUAAUUCAAAUUGAGUUUCACCAUCAUACUGGGACCCCCACCUGAUGUGGUUUCGUUGCCCAUUUUUCAAAUAUGUAUUAUUUGUGGCUUACAUUAACAUCUUAGAUUUCACUCUGACUUCCUCACCAGUCAGUCUUAAUCUGCUAUAAUAUGGCCAUCACUCCAUAUGGUUGAAACUGUUGGUAUCCAAAUUACAAGUGACUUAAUGUCUAAAUCCACUGGAUGCAUUCUACUUGUUAAUAUAUUUGACACACAUAAACACUCACACUGACACACAUAAGUACUUCUUAAAACUCUCUCCUCCAUGGGUUGGAACUAUAGUCUCUUGGACUUUUCUUUCCCUACUCUAACCCGUCUUCUCAGUUUCCUCCAAAGACUCGCUUUCCUUCACCUACUCAUUACAUGUUAGUGUUCCCCCAAAGUUCCACCUGUUGUCAUCUCGUCUCUAUACUCUAACAUCCUUGGUGAUCCCAUCUACAACUCCUAUGUCAGCUACCAUUGUUGGUGCUAAUGCCGUCUAUGUCCGUGUCCCAACAUCAGAUCUCCAUGAGAUGUUCCAGAAAUACAUAUGCUAUUAUCUUUUGGAUUUUUAUCCAAAGAUAGUAUAAGUAUAUAUAUAUAUAUAUAAAAUAUUUGAUAUAUCCAAAGAUAGUUUAUAUAUAAGCACCUGAAUCAAAACUUACCAUCUCAUAAAAGUAGUUCUUCCUCCAGUUCCUAUCUCAGUGAAUGGCAUGUCCUGUUAGAAAAUCACCAUAUUUUACUUUUCUCCAUCAUUCUCCAAGUCCAGCCGAGUCAAUUCUUACUUGAUUUUAUCAUCCAAAUAUCUAAGUAAUUCACCUCUUCCCCAUCUUUAUCUCUGCCUCAUUACUUAAUUCUUGUCCUUAUUUGACAUUGGGAUUUCUAAAAUAACCUCUUACUGGUGUUCCUGCCUCCAGUUCCUUCCUUUUACUGUUAGCAGUGUAGUCUUUGUUAAACCCCAAAUUUAGCACGUCACCCUAACUUAAACUCCUGACUGCAUACAGGUAGAAAUCAAAAUUCCCCACUAAAGCCCAUAGGGCCUUUAAUGAUGUGGUCUGGCCUACCUCUCCAGCCUGUUCUCUAACCACUGUCCCACCCUAUAUCUUUCUGUUCAGUCUUACAAAACUAUUUCAUAAAAAUUUUCUCACUUCUCUGCCUUUGCACAGGCUGUUUGAUAUACCUGGAGUAAUCCCCACCAUUGAUUCUUUUCUUGGCAAAAAUCUAUUGUAAAACUUAUCAUCUUGGCCUGGAAACAAUCCAUAACUUCUACUGUUCUGGAUUAAGUGACUUUUUAGAUGUUCUUGUAGUUCUUUGUAUAGACCUCUCUCAAAACUGUCAUAUGACAUUAAAUUGUCUAUUUUAUUUGUGUGUUUGCCCCUUUACACUGUGAACUUCUUAAUGGCAGGGACCAUUUUUUAUUUAUUUUUGUGUCUUCAAAACCUGGCACACACUAGAUGCUCUAUAAAGAUUUGUUAAAUUAUUUCUAUAGUUAUUUAUUUUAAUCCUACACAGAAUGUAUAAAAAUAAUUUACUAUAUUGUUAGUGAAGAAGAUUGUAUCAAAAUGCAGUAUACAAUCCUUAAGGUAUGUGGGAUGCUUGAUAGUAAUACAAAUGUAUGAAUAAUUGUUCCAGUCUUCUCCAAACCUGUAAGAGGGAAAUAGGAAAAUAAAAAUGUUUUGUUUUAUUGUUUUGAACUCUUGAAAAUAAACUUAACCUCAAAAAUA